AUGUAUUUAACUUCCAGGGUGAAAAGGAACAGCCUGUAUUUGCAAUGACCGGCCUUCGAUGGGGAUCUUUCAGAGAUGCUGGCGUCAAAGUUAGCAAGUACUGGUAUCUUGGGCCUCUAAAAAUCAAAGCAGCCCACUUUUUCAGCACUCUUAAGGAGUGGCCUCAGACUCAUCAAGCCUCUAUCUCAUACACGGGACCUACAGAGAGACCUCCCAAUGAACCAGAGGAGACCCCUGUACAAAGGCCUUCUUUGUACAGGAGAAUAUUACGAAGGCUUGCGUCCUACUGGGCACAACCACAGGAUGCCCUUUCCCAAGAGGUGAGCCCGGAGGUCUGGAAAGAUGUGCAGCUGUCCACCAUUGAACUGUCCAUCACAACACGGAAUAAUCAGCUUGACCCGACAAGCAAAGAAGAUUUUCUGAAUAUCUGCAUUGAACCUGACACCAUCAGCAAAGGAGACUUUAUAACUAUAGGAAGUCGAAAGGUGAGAAACCCCAAGCUGCACGUGGAGGGCACGGAGUGUCUCCAAGCCAGCCAGUGCACUUUGCUUAUCCCGGAGGGAGCAGGGGGCUCUUUUAGCAUUGACAGUGAGGAGUAUGAAGCGAUGCCUGUGGAGGUGAAACUGCUCCCCAGGAAGCUGCAGUUCUUCUGUGAUCCUAGGAAGAGAGAACAGAUGCUCACAAGCCCCACCCAGUGAGCAGCAGAAGACAAGCACUCUGAGACCACACUUUAGGCCACCGGUGGGACCAAAAGGGAACAGGUGCCUCAGCCAUCCCAACAGUGUCGUCAGAGGGUCCCCAGGGCAUUUUCAUGGCAAGUACCCCUCUGCCCCCACUCCAGCAGUGCUUCCCAAAGUGUGCUCUGUCACCUGCUUUGCAAUCGGCUUCCAUUAGCGCAUGUUUUAUUUUGGUGUGACGGUUGGCCCUCCUAAACACGGACUUUCCUCAGGCUGGUUCAAGACGGAAAAGGACUUUCUUCUGUUUUCUUCCAAAGUGCAACCACAGUGGAGAGCCCACGGUGGGCUUAGCCUGCCUAGGCCCUUCCAUUUCUCUUCUUUGACCGUGCUAGGAAUUCCAGGAAAGUGCAUUCCUGCCCUGGUGACCUUUUCCUAUGUCUAGGCUCCUCCACAGGUGCUGCUAUUUUGUGAGCUCCGGCUCCUGUUUAGCUUUUAUUUCAGUUCUAACCUCAGUCCAGAAACAUAUGUGAGGUUGUUUCCCUCUUCAGCCACGGCUACAAUACCGGAAAAUGCUAGUUUUUAUUUAUUUUUUUAAGUAGUGCUUCCUAAAUGGUUUGCAUGAGAGCCACCUGGGGUACAUGUUGAAAACUUAUUUGGGGUCUACCCCAAACCUAAUAACCCAAAUUUGGGGAUGGGGCCCAGGAAUAUGCAUUUUUAAAAAGUCAUCUGCCCUUCCCAGGUGAUUCUGUAAGUUGUCCCUCAACUGUACUUGGAGAAAUCGUGUUUUAAAGCAGUAGUCCACAAAGUAUUCUGCUCAUGUGCCCCCAAAAGUAUUUUGAAAAAUCAUGUAUACCCUCACCCAUCUAAGUUGAUAUCUAAAAUUUUAUCUAAGUUGGUAUCUAAAAUUUUUCAUGGGAAGUUAAAUAGUUGACAAAGUAUGUAUUUGCUGGUGUCGUGUAAAUAUUGGUAUUUUAAAAUAAAAACUGUUACAUCACUAUUUUAAACAUAUCCAGUACAAUUUAAAUAUCACAACAAUUUGACACCCUUCAUUCAUUUAUAAAAAUAAAUGAGCUAGUUCUUUAGUAGUUAAACAUUUCAAAUUGGCUUUUCUCCUUCUGUAUUUCCAUACCACUUUUCAGCCAAGAAUCCUAUCAUAAUGUAAUCUAUUAUGCCCGACAUCUUUUAAUCAUUCACCCCAUUACUUCUUGUCAACAAAAAAUAUAAAUGGAAAUUUUUUUUUUAGCUCUUGCUUUAAGUGUUUGUUUGUUAUCUCAGUCCAGAACCAAUAUUAUCGUAAUUAAUUAUUGGUAUAUAAUGAAAACGGUAUUAAUUCUUGGAUGAUUAAAAGUUUUUUUAUUAGAAUGUUCUUUAUCCUAAUUAGUUCAUUUAUCCAAGAAUACAUGAAUGUGAUUUACAGCUGAGAUGGGGUUCAACCUCAGCUGUAUUCCUUGUUUCUGUAUAGAUGUAAGCACAUAAAUUCGAUGGAAUAGAAUUACGUUAACAAUGUUUUUACAGUUCUUUGGAUUCCUUUGGCAUUUUGACAAAGAUCACAGUGCUCUAUCAUCAAGAAUUAUUAAUGAUGAUCUAUCAACUAACAAACAACUUGAUUAGAUUCUCCUUUAGUCUGUUGAAAGCAGAGAACUGAAAUCCACCUGAUUUACCAUGGCUUUGCCAGCCAGUCAUUAGCACCAUUUACUUUUACUAUCGCUGACAUUUUCCUUUGUUCAGUGGCCCUGAGGUUCUUACACUCUAGGGGGCAGUGCACCACAGGAAGAUAGAUCAAUGAGGGAGGAUUGCGAGGGGGAAGGGGAGGAAGCAGAGCUGGCAGGCCUUAGCUACAGGCUCUCUCUCAGGCAGAUCCCUUUUAAGAUACAUACACCAUGCCCACACAUCCCAUGGAGAGAGACCAAUGCUUUAGUAGAUUACAGAACAGCUAUGAAAAGUCCAUGAAUGAAGAUCACAAAAAGGAAGGCUUUCUUAUUUCAUACUGUAUUCUUCAGGGUGGUAAAAUUUCUGCUUUUGGCAAAAACAUAACAGACGGUUCCAAACAUCAGCAUAAAGAUCACUCAUCCCAUACCACCCACAGGUAGGGAGGAAGGAUGCUGUAGUAUAUGAAAACAAAAGUUUUCACCUGAGCUGAGAGCAUUUAGCAUAUCGUGGUUCUGUAACAAUAUCAAGGACCAGUGCAGAAUCUGGCUUUCUUUUCUGAUAGGCUACCAGUGUGUGUUUAUGUGUGCUCAUUUUGUGGUUCUAAUCAUAAUGGUACAUAUAAUUAGGGAAGGAUAUGGAAGCCACUUUAGAAUCUUAUUCAUUUUUAAAUAUAAAUAUGCCUUGUUUCAAA